GGAUAUCUGAAGACGCCGUUUCCUGCGCGUCCUGUAUCUAUGGAGACGGCAAUAUGGAGGCGAUCUUACAUUUCUUUGAUUUCAUCUGAACGUCCAGUUCACAAUUGGAGAAUGUUUUAAAGUACACAUGUGGAUUGCAUUAUAUUUUGGGGGGCAGUGCCAUGUUCUAUGAUUUCAUGCAUGAUGGCUUCAUGUCAAGUGUAAAGGGAAAUCAGAGAUGAACCAUUUGAGGUAAGUCAUUAUAGGGAUCUGCAAACCACUUCCACAUGUGCCUGAGUGGGGCUGGCUUAGUCUUGGUGUGUGAGUGUGAAAAUUGCUGUCCUUUUGUCGAGGUAACAAAGUCACACUUGAGUGUGUGUGCUAAAAGAAGCCAGCUAAAGGAAGAGGGGAUUCGAGGUGAGGGAGCCAGAGCUAGUCUGAGAUACUUUGUGUGCCUUAGAUUGAGGUCAAGCAUCCUCUUGAGCAUUUGGUGAAAACUGUGGCCAUUCCUCCUGGAAAACAGACAUGUAUGCAUACAUAGCAUCUGGCAUAUACAUAGCAUCUGGCAUAUAUACAAAUAUAUGUGCCACAUAUAUUUGCAUAUGAUUUCAGCUACAGUCAUCGAGGAUCCCUCUGCUCUGGAGAUGGAUUGACUUAUGCUUUGAUUGAUUUAUUUCAGUGAUGUUUACCUUAACCGGUUGUAGACUGGUGGAGAAAACCCAGAAGGUGGAGAAUCCAUCAGUCUCAUUUGCCUCUUCUUUCCCCCUUAUUCCUCUUCUCCUAAGAGGCAAGAGUGUUCAGAAGAAACAAGCAGAGAGUAAAAGCCAGAUAAAGCUCCAUACUCAGAGUGCUCCCUUUGGACUGUGUCCCAAGGACAUGAUGCUCACCCAGGCUCCAAGCUCCGUCGUGAGGUCCAGGAACAGCAGGAACCACACCGUGAACUCUGGUGGAUCCUGCCUGAGUGCCAGCACAGUGGCCAUCCCUGCCAUCAACGACAGCAGUGCAGCCAUGAGUGCCUGCAGCACCAUCAGCGCCCAGCCCGCAAGCUCCAUGGACACUCAGAUGCACUCCCCAAAGAAGCAGGAGAGAGUGAACAAGAGGGUCAUCUGGGGCAUUGAGGUGGCUGAGGAGCUGCAUUGGAAAGGCUGGGAGCUAGGAAAGGAGACCACAAGGAAUCUGGUUCUGAAAAAUCGAUCCUUGAAACUCCAGAAGAUGAAGUACAGGCCCCCCAAGACCAAGUUCUUCUUCACGGUCAUCCCUCAGCCCAUCUUCCUGAGCCCAGGCAUAACCCUCACGCUCCCCAUCGUCUUCCGGCCUCUGGAGGCGAAGGAGUACAUGGACCAGCUGUGGUUUGAGAAAGCGGAGGGGAUGUUCUGUGUCGGCCUACGGGCCACCCUGCCCUGCCACAGGCUGAUCUGCCGCCCACCAUCCCUGCAGCUGCCCAUGUGUGCUGUGGGAGAUACGACUGAGGCCUUUUUCUGCCUGGAUAAUGUGGGGGACCUGCCCACCUUCUUCACCUGGGAGUUCUCCAGCCCAUUCCAGAUGCUGCCCGCCACGGGGCUCCUGGAGCCAGGCCAGGCCUCUCAGAUCAAGGUGACCUUUCAGCCCCUUACAGCCGUCAUCUACGAGGUGCAGGCCACGUGCUGGUACGGGGCGGGCAGCCGGCAGAGGAGCAGCAUCCAGCUGCAGGCUGUGGCCAAGUGCGCCCAGCUGCUGGUGAGCAUAAAGCACAAGUGCCCGGAGGACCAGGAUGCCGAGGGCUUCCAGAAGCUGUUGUACUUUGGCUCUGUUGCUGUGGGCUGCACCUCGGAGAGGCAGAUCAGGCUACACAACCCGUCGGCGGUAAAUGCCCCCUUCAGGAUUGAAAUUUCCCCGGAUGAACUGGCCGAAGACCAGGCCUUCUCAUGCCCCACGGCCCAUGGCAUCGUGCUUCCGGGAGAGAAGAAAUGUGUGUCGGUGUUCUUCCACCCCAAGACUCUGGACACCAGAACUGUGGACUACUGCUCCAUCAUGCCUUCUGGCUGUGCCUCCAAGACCCUGCUUAAAGUCGUUGGUUUCUGUAGAGGCCCUGCUGUGUCCCUGCAGCACUACUGUGUCAACUUCAGCUGGGUCAACCUUGGGGAGCGCUCCGAGCAGCCCCUGUGGAUUGAGAACCAAUCGGACUGCACGGCCCACUUCCAGUUUGCCAUCGACUGCUUGGAGAGUGUCUUUACCAUCAGGCCUGCCUUUGGGACGCUGGUGGGCAAGGCCCGUAUGACCCUGCACUGUGCCUUCCAGCCCACUCACCCCAUCAUCUGCUUUCGGCGUGUGGCCUGUCUCAUCCACCACCAGGACCCACUGUUCCUGGACCUGAUGGGGACCUGCCACUCGGACAGCACCAAGCCAGCCAUCCUGAAGCCUCAGCACCUCACCUGGUACCGCACACACCUGGCCCGGGGCCUGACGCUCUACCCCCCUGACAUCCUGGAUGCCAUGCUGAAGGAGAAGAAGCUGGCACAGGACCAGAACGGGGCUCUCAUGAUUCCCAUCCAGGAUCUGGAGGACAUGCCGGCCCCGCAGUACCCUUAUAUCCCCCCCAUGACCGAGUUCUUCUUCGACGGCACCAGCGACAUAACCAUCUUCCCCCCGCCCAUCAGUGUAGAGCCUGUCGAGGUAGACUUCGGUGCCUGCCCAGGGCCUGAGGCCCCCAACCCUGUACCCCUGUGCCUGAUGAACCACACCAAGGGCAAGAUCAUGGUGGUCUGGACGCGAAGGUCUGACUGCCCCUUCUGGGUGACUCCAGAGAGCUGCGACGUGCCCCCACUCAAGUCCAUGGCCAUGCGCCUGCACUUCCAGCCGCCUCACCCCAACUGCCUUUACACGGUGGAGCUCGAAGCCUUCGCCAUCUAUAAGGUCCUGCAGAGCUACAGUAAUAUUGAGGAGGACUGCACCAUGUGCCCAUCCUGGUGCCUGACGGUGCGGGCACGAGGCCACAGCUAUUUCGCUGGCUUUGAGCACCACAUCCCCCAGUAUUCCCUAGAUGUCCCCAAGCUAUUUCCAGCAGUGUCCUCCGGUGAGCCCACCUACCGCAGCCUGCUCCUGGUCAACAAAGACUGCAAGCUGCUGACCUUCAGCCUGGCCCCCCAGAGAGGCUCAGACGUCAUCCUUCGGCCCACUUCGGGCCUUGUGGCACCCGGGGCCCACCAGAUCAUCCUCAUCUGCACCUACCCUGAGGGCAGCUCCUGGAAGCAGCACACUUUCUAUCUGCAGUGCAAUGCUUCCCCCCAGUAUCUCAAGGAGGUGAGCAUGUACAGCCGGGAGGAGCCACUGCAGCUGAAGCUGGACACCCACAAAAGCCUCUACUUCAAGCCCACCUGGGUGGGCUGCUCCUCCACCAGCCCCUUCACCUUCCGCAACCCCUCGCGUCUGCCCCUGCAGUUCGAGUGGAGGGUCUCUGAGCAGCAUCGAAAGCUGCUGGCUGUCCAGCCCUCCAGGGGGCUAAUCCAGCCCAACGAGAGACUUACGCUGACGUGGACCUUCAGCCCUUUGGAGGAGACCAAGUACCUGUUCCAAGUGGGGAUGUGGGUCUGGGAAGCCGGCCUGUCCCCAAAUGCCAACCCCGCUGCCACCACCCACUACAUGCUCCGGCUGGUGGGCGUUGGGCUCACCAGCAGCCUCUCUGCAAAGGAAAAGGAGCUGGCCUUUGGGAAUGUGCUGGUGAACAGCAAGCAGUCCAGGUUCCUUGUCCUCCUGAAUGACGGCAACUGCACCCUCUAUUACCGCCUCUACCUGGAGCAGGGCAGCCCUGAGGCCGUUGACAACCACCCCCUCGCUCUGCAGCUGGACCGAACAGAGGGGAGCAUGCCACCCCGGUCCCAGGACACCAUCUGCCUGACUGCCUGUCCCAAGCAGCGGUCCCAGUACUCCUGGACCAUCACCUACUCUCUCCUUUCCCACAGAGAUAACAAGGCUGGGGAGAAGCAGGAGCUGUGCUGCGUCUCCCUGGUGGCCGUGUACCCCUUGCUUUCCAUCCUGGAUGUCAGCUCCAUGGGCAGUGCUGAGGGUAUCACCCGGAAGCACCUGUGGCGCCUCUUCUCUCUGGACCUGCUUAACAGUUACUUGGAGCGUGACCCCACCCCCUGUGAGCUCACCUACAAGGUGCCCACCCGGCACAGCAUGAGCCAGAUCCCCCCCGUCCUCACCCCUUUAAGGCUUGACUUCAAUUUCGGGGCCGCACCAUUCAAGGCCCCACCUUCCGUGGUAUUCCUGGCCCUGAAGAACAGCGGAGUGGUGUCCCUGGACUGGGCCUUCCUCCUUCCAAGUGACCAGCGGAUUGACGUGGAGCUCUGGGCAGAGCAAGCAGAGUUGAAUUCCACUGAGCUCCACCAGAUGCGCGUGCAGGACAAUUGCCUCUUCUCCAUCAGCCCCAAGGCUGGGAGCCUGAGUCCUGGGCAGGAGCAGAUGGUGGAGUUAAAAUACAGCCACCUGUUCAUCGGUACUGAUCACCUCCCAGUGCUCUUCAAGGUGUCCCAUGGCCGGGAGAUCCUGCUAAAUUUCAUAGGUGUGACAGUGAAGCCGGAGCAGAAGUAUGUGCACUUCACCUCUACUACCCACCAGUUCAUCCCCAUUCCCAUUGGUGACACGCUACCCCCACGGCAGAUUUAUGAGCUGUAUAAUGGUGGCUCAGUGCCCGUGACAUAUGAGGUCCAGACCGAUGUCCUGUCACAGGUUCAGGAAAAAAAUUUUGAUCACCCCAUCUUUUGCUGCCUCAACCCCAAAGGGGAGAUCCAGCCAGGCAGCACUGCCCGGGUCUUGUGGAUCUUCUCACCUAUCGAGGCCAAGACCUACACGGUGGACGUGCCCAUACACAUCCUGGGAUGGAACUCGGCCCUCAUCCACUUCCAGGGAGUGGGCUACAACCCCCAUAUGAUGGGGGACACAGCCCCAUUCCACAACAUCUCCUCGUGGGACAACAGUUCCAUACACUCUAGGCUGGUGGUGCCUGGACAGAAUGUCUUCCUGUCCCAGUCUCAUAUUUCCCUGGGAAACAUACCUGUGCAGAGCAAGUGCAGCCGCCUGCUCUUCCUCAACAACAUCUCCAAGAACGAGGAAAUUGCCUUCUCCUGGCAGCCAAGUCCUCUAGAUUUUGGGGAGGUGUCUGUGAGUCCCAUGAUAGGGGUGGUGGCUCCUGAAGAGACGGUCCCAUUUGUGGUGACCUUGAGGGCCUCUGUGCAUGCCAGCUUCUACAGUGCAGACCUGGUAUGCAAGCUGUACUCGCAGCAGCUCAUGAGGCAGUAUCACAAGGAGCUGCAGGAGUGGAAGGACGAGAAGGUGCGGCAGGAAGUGGAGUUCACCAUCACCGACAUGAAAGUGAAGAAGAGAACAUGCUGCACAGCCUGUGAACCUGCGAGGAAGUACAAGACACUGCCUCCCAUCAAGAACCAGCAGUCUGUCAGCCGGCCUGCCAGCUGGAAACUGCAGACCCCAAAGGAGGAGGUGUCCUGGCCCUGCCCCCAGCCACCCUCGCCAGGCAUGCUCUGCCUGGGCCUUACUGCCCGAGCCCAUGCCACCGACUACUUUCUGGCUAACUUCUUCUCAGAGUUUCCCUGCCACUUUUUGCACCGCAUGGUGGCUUGCCCAGGCCACUCAGAAUGUCAUGGCUGCCACAGGGAGCUGCCAAAGAGGAAGGCCCCCAGGGAAGAGUCAGAGACUUCUGAGGAAAAAUCCCCUAACAAGUGGGGCCCUGUUUCCAAGCAGAAGAAGCAGCUCCUGGUUGACAUUCUCACCACAAUAAUCAGGGGCCUGCUGGAAGACAAGAACUUCCAUGAGGCUGUGGACCAAAGCCUGGUGGAGCAGGUGCCGUACUUCCGCCAAUUCUGGAAUGAGCAGUCAACUAAGUUCAUGGACCAGAAAAACAGCCUGUACUUAAUGCCAAUCCUGCCUGUACCCUCCAGCAGCUGGGAGGAUGGGAAGGGCAAGCAGCCGAAGGAAGACAGACCAGAGCACUAUCCAGGGUUGGGAAAGAAGGAAGAGGGGGAGGAGGAGAAGGGUGAAGAGGAAGAAGAAGAGUUGGAGGAGGAAGAGGAGGAAGAAGAGGAGACAGAAGAGGAGGAGUUGGGCAAGGAGGAGAUAGAGGAGAAGGAGGAGGAGAGGGAUGAGAAGGAAGAGAAAGUGAGCUGGGCGGGCAUCGGGCCCACACCACAGCCUGAGUCCCAGGAGUCCAUGCAAUGGCAGUGGCAACAGCAGCUGAAUGUCAUGGUGAAGGAGGAGCAAGAACAGGACGAGAAGGAGGCCAUCAGAAGGCUCCCGGCCUUCGCCAACCUGCAGGAGGCGCUGCUGGAGAACAUGAUCCAGAACAUCCUGGUGGAGGCGAGCCGCGGGGAGGUGGUACUCACCUCGCGGCCACGCGUCAUCGCCCUGCCGCCGUUCUGCGUGCCCAGGAGUCUGACCCCGGACACGCUGCUGCCGACGCAGCAAGCAGAGGUACUCCACCCGGUGGUGCCACUUCCUACCGACCUUCCGUAAAUGCCCGCGCCCAGCCUCUCCGACAUGCCGCUAGGGGUCACGCCUGGCCCCCUCUCCACCGCCAGUAAAAGCAUCUAGUCUUUUUUCUGUA